CCUCUACCUGCUCCACCCUCAAUCCACCAGAACCAUGGGCUGUUGCGGCUGCUCCGGAGGCUGUGGCUCCAGCUGUGGGGGCUGUGGCUCCGGCUGUGGGGGCUGUGGCUCCGGCUGUGGGGGCUGUGGCUCUGGCUGUGGAGGUUCUGGCUCCAGCUGCUGUGUGCCCGUCUGCUGCUGCAAGCCCGUGUGCUGCCGUGUGCCAACCUGUUCCUGCUCCAGCUGUGGCAAAGGGGGCUGUGGCUCUUCUGGGGGCUCCAAGGGGGGCUGUGGCUCCUGUGGAGGCUGCAAGGGGGGCUGUGGCUCUUGUGGGGGAUCCAAGGGGGGUUGUGGCUCCUGUGGGGGCUCCAAGGGGGGCUGUGGCUCUUGUGGGGGAUCCAAGGGUGGCUGUGGUUCCGGCUGUGGGGGAUGUGGCUCCAGCUGCUGUGUGCCUGUCUGCUGCUGCAAGCCCAUGUGCUGCUGUGUGCCAGCUUGUUCCUGCUCCAGCUGUGGCAAAGGGGGCUGUGGCUCCUGUGGGUGCUCCAAGGGGGCCUGUGGUUCUUGUGGGGGCUCCAAGGGGGGCUGUGGCUCCUGUGGAGGCUGCAAGGGGGGCUGCGGUUCUUGUGGGGGAUCCAAGGGGGGUUGUGGCUCCGGCUGUGGGGGCUGUGGCUCCGGCUGCGGUGUGCCCGUGUGUUGCUGUUCCUGUUCCAGUUGUGGCUCUUGCGCGGGGUCUAAGGGAGGCUGCGGGUCAUCCUGCUCCCAGUGCAGUUGCUGUAAGCCCUGCUGCUGUUCCUCAGGCUGUGGGUCAUCCUGUUGCCAAUCCAGCUGCUGCAAGCCCUGCUGCUCCCAGUCCAGUUGCUGUGUCCCCGUGUGCUGCCAGUGCAAGAUCUGAUUUCUGGCUUUGCAGGACUCUUACCAUGGCCAGGCAUUCCUGCCCAGCCUUUACCUCCUUUUCCUGGCACC